GCCGGACCCGCUAAGGCCGCCCUCCGGGUAGCCGCCAUGUCGGUCUCCAGCGGCGUCCAGAUUCUGACAAAGCCAGAGACCGUGGACCGGAGGAGAAGUGCGGAAACGACCAAAGAGGCCGGGCGACCACUGGAGAUGGCUGUGUCCGAGCCCGAGGCCAGCGCCGCGGUAUCAGUAACAUUCAAACAUGUGACUAUGGCCUUUACCCAGAAGGAAUGGAAGCAACUGGAUCCUGCUCAGAGCAACCUGUAUAAUGAUGUGAUGCUGGAGAACUACUGCAACCAAGCCUCAAUGGGGUGUCAAGCUCCCAAACCAGACAUGAUCUCCAAGUUGGAAAAAGGAGAAGCACCAUGGUUGGGGAAGGGGAAAAGACCCAGUCAAGGUUGUCCAAGUAAAAUAGCAAGACCCAAGCAAAAAGAAACUGAUGGAAAAGUCCAGAAAGAUGAUGACCAGCUUGAAAAUAUCCAGAAAUCUCAAAACAAACUCCUCAGGGAAGUUGCAGUCAAGAAGAAAACUCAAGCUAAGAAGAAUGGCAGUGACUGUGGUUCACUGGGGAAAAAAAAUAAUUUGCAUAAAAAACAUGUUCCUUCAAAGAAAAGGCUUCUUAAAUUUGAGUCAUGUGGAAAAAUUUUGAAACAGAAUUUAGAUUUACCUGAUCACUCAAGAAACUGUGUAAAAAGGAAAUCUGAUGCAGCUAAAGAACACAAGAAGUCAUUCAACCAUAGCUUAUCUGAUACAAGGAAAGGCAAAAAGCAAACUGGAAAGAAACAUGAGAAAUUAUCCAGCCAUAGCUCAUCUGAUAAGUGUAACAAAACUGGCAAAAAACAUGACAAAUUAUGCUGUCAUAGUUCAUCCCAUAUUAAACAGGACAAAAUUCAAACUGGAGAGAAACAUGAGAAAUCACCCAGCCUUAGCUCAUCUACUAAGCAUGAAAAACCUCAAGCUUGUGUGAAACCCUAUGAAUGUAAUCAAUGUGGAAAGGUUCUCAGCCAUAAACAAGGACUCAUUGACCAUCAGAGAGUUCAUACUGGGGAGAAACCAUAUGAAUGUAAUGAAUGUGGGAUAGCCUUUAGCCAAAAGUCACACCUUGUUGUACAUCAGAGAACUCACACCGGAGAAAAACCAUAUGAAUGUAUUCAGUGUGGCAAAGCCCAUGGUCAUAAACAUGCACUCACUGACCAUCUAAGAAUUCAUACUGGAGAAAAGCCCUAUGAAUGUGCUGAAUGUGGGAAAACCUUCAGACACAGCUCAAACCUUAUUCAACAUGUGAGAUCUCACACAGGUGAGAAGCCAUAUGAAUGUAAGGAAUGUGGGAAGUCUUUUAGGUAUAACUCAUCUCUUACCGAACAUGUGAGAACACAUACAGGUGAAAUACCAUAUGAAUGCAAUGAAUGUGGAAAAGCCUUUAAGUAUAGCUCAUCCCUUACUAAACACAUGAGAAUUCAUACAGGUGAGAAACCCUUUGAAUGUAAUGAAUGUGGGAAAGCUUUCAGCAAGAAGUCACACCUCAUUAUACAUCAAAGAACUCAUACUAAGGAGAAACCUUAUAAAUGUAAUGAGUGUGGAAAAGCCUUUGGACAUAGCUCAUCUCUUACUUACCAUAUGAGAACUCAUACAGGUGAAAGUCCCUUUGAAUGUAAUCAAUGUGGGAAAGGCUUUAAACAAAUUGAAGGCCUUACUCAACAUCAGAGAGUUCAUACUGGAGAGAAACCGUAUGAGUGUAAUGAAUGUGGGAAAGCCUUUAGCCAAAAGUCUCACCUCAUUGUACAUCAGAGAACUCAUACUGGGGAGAAACCUUAUGAAUGUAACGAAUGUGAAAAAGCCUUUAAUGCAAAAUCACAGCUUGUUAUACAUCAGCGAUCCCACACUGGAGAAAAACCCUAUGAAUGUAAUGAAUGUGGGAAAACUUUCAAACAAAAUGCAUCCCUAACCAAACAUGUGAAAACUCAUUCAGAAGAUAAAUCUCAUGAGUGAAGUUAAUGUGGGAAAUUUGUUAACUAAAUUUAAGGUUUUGUUGAACCUUGGAAAUAUGCUGAUUUUAAAGAGUGUUAGAAAGCCUUUAGCAAGAUGUCACACCUUGUUGUACAUGAGAAACUUUGAAAAUGGAUCUUCAUAUAGAAUCAGUGGAUGGAAACAAGGGUUUAAACUUGAUACAAAACCUUUUAUAAAAAAUAUUGUUUUAACUACUCAAUUAUUAUAAAUGAUCUACAUGUUCAGAUUGAAAUUGAAAGCUUUAAAAAUUGUGAAUUAUUUGAAUAUUCAAAGCAAUGGAGAAACAAGUUAUAUAUGCUGACAGUUCCUGUGUUUCUUCUUGUUUUGUACUUAAGCACCAUAUAUUAGAGUUGAAUUUGCAUAUCUGUUUAUUGCCUUAUGUAAAUGAGUGUGGCCAUCUGUAUAAGCCUCUUUGACAUUUUCACCCAGCUCUUUCUUAAUGUCUGUGUUGGCUUCUGCAUCAGCAGAAAUCUUUUUAAAAGGGUUGUUAUAUAUGUAAAAAAUGUUAACAGGAAAAUGAGAGAAAAUAAAGCAGCUGAGGAUACAAAUGUGCUGGUAGGGAGCGAUAUUCAAGAUAUAUUGUGAAGUGUGAAAAAGUAGGUUGCUGAACCAUGUAUAUAGUAUGUUCCCCUUUGUGUACAAAAGGGUAUGUUUGUUUAACCUCUGUCUCUUAUCUCUGUAUGUGUAUGUAUCUUUGUAUGCAUAUAUACAUGUAUCUGUAUGUGAAUAGACUUUGAAAAAAUACAGAAUAAACUUCAUGGUGGUUGCCAUUGGGCAGAGGAGUAUAGGACUGGGGUCUAGGAUAGGAGCAAGACUUCCUUGUAUAUUUGGAUUUUUAAAUCAUGCACAUGUAUUAUUUUUAUAAUUAAAAUAUUUUAAUAUGCAUAAAUCAACAUUAUUUAAGGUUGUCACUGAGCCCCUCCACAACAUGUGAGAUCAACAUGUGAGAUCUCAGAUUUUGACAGAGUUAAAAUCUUUGUAUGCUUAUUCAUGAAUGAUGAUGAAUCUAAAGUAUAUAGUAUGAAACUUGAUGUUGAAUUCAUAAAGACUUUUUCUAUCACACACAAGUUCUUUCAUUAACAUAGUGAAUUAUAACAGCACUGUUUCUACAUUUGCCAUUUUUUGAUGUUGAAUUGUGAUUGCAGGUGAUGAUGAAUUGUGAUUGCAGGUGAAUGAAAGUGAUUUUAUGAAUAAUCACCCUGUUUUAUCUCAUAUUCAAAGAACUAACACACAAACACCUCAAUCAGGGAAUUCGAAUGAAACAAAUGUCACCCCUCCCUGUUCUCGCUCAAUAUUGGGCAUUAUUUACUGGAUCACUGUACUCUUUCUGAGUGAACCCAGAGUUGGCCUCAGAAUCAUUGUGCAGCGUGCAUUCCAGAAGGUACUAUGCAUCAACUUGGACUGUCACAGGAGACCUAUUUGCCAUUGCACACCUGGAUUUUUUUUACUCUUGAGCCAUAGAUUAAAAAUACUUCUGGCUGGGCAUGGUGGGUGCCUGUAAUCUCCAGCACUGUGGGAGGCCAAGGUGGGUGGAUCACUUGAGGCCAGGAGUUUGAGAUCAGACUAGCCAACACAAUGAAACCCCAUCUCUACUAAAAAUACAAAAAAUUAUCUGGGCAUGCUGUAAUCCCUGUAAUCCCAGCCACUCAGGAGGCUGAGGCAAGAGAGUUGCUUGCACCCAGGAGAUGGAGGUUACAGUGCACUCCAGCCUGGGCAGCAGAGUGAGGCUCUGUCUCAAAAAAAAGAAAUACAAAAAAUGCACAAAACUUCUGAACUAUUUUGAAAUCUAAGUUGUUACACUAAAAGCAGAGACAUAAGUACAGAAAUGGUUUUCAAAAACAUCAUACCUUUAUUUUAAUACAAUAUUAAUUUACAUAAUAUAAAAUAUUAUAAUUUGGCAUGUUAUCUUUUAUAUUUUUUAAAGCACAAUCCCUACAUUAUUUCAUUUAUUCCUCAGAACUAACAUAUGAGCAGUAAUCGGGACUUGUCUAGUCAUGUUCAAUCCUGUUGAGUAAAUAUUUCACCUAGACAGUAAUUUAGCAUAAUAAUGGGCCCCAAAGAAAUAUGUGCUUAAAUGCCAUCUUUACAAAUAUUUAUCAUUCAAGCUCCUUCCUUCCUGACCUCAUUUCAGAGAAUUAUAAUGUGUUAAUAUAAUAUAUUGAGAAUGGAAUAUGUGUUCGUGUAUGUGCAUGUGCACACAUGCAUACACAUGCACGGGUUGAAAGCUCAACUCAUGAAUAUAUCCCCUCAUUUCCAAGUAACUUAUUUAUCACAUGGGAAGAAAAUGCAAUAUGAAAGCCAUUUCUACCAGUAAUUUCUUAACAAGUGGAAAUAUAGCACUAUGCACAGAAUGAGUCAUCACUGUCUAGAGCUGUAGAAAGCCUGCACUUUUUAGAUGGAUGAAACAGUUGCAGGUUAUGGCUAUGUUGAAUUUCCACAUGUCUUGGGGAACCCAUAGUAUUGCCACAUCUGAGACAGUGAGAAUUAUAGGUAUGCCUGAAUGAUAUAAAUGAAUGCUGAAAGCCACUUUGUGCAGUAAUAAAAUGAAUUAAAAGUUAGCAUUGAUGAAUGAGGAAAGGAUGUCUAAAUACAAUUGGAGGUUAGUAUAGGAAAACAGACACACAGUGGUAAGUCUGAAUCGAUACGUAAACUCUAGUGUGCAUAAAAAUUGCCUGAAUGAUUUGUUAAAACACAGACUUGAGAAUGCAAAUUCUUGGGCCUCGUCACAGACAUAUUGGAUCAGAAACCCUGUGGGUGGGCCUUGAGAAUUUGCAUUUUAAUAAGUUUCCAGUGGAUUCCUGUGCUGCUGGUCUGGGGACCACCCUUUGAGAACCACUAAUCUAAAUCAUGGUGUAAGUAAGUUUAAAAAAUUAUUUUUAAACUGUUUUUCAGAUCCUCUUUAAGAAAAUGAAGGGGCAUAAAAGUAAAUUAUUAUUAACAGUUUUGAAACAUUUAUUUAUUCAAGUGAUAUGAUCAUCUAAGUGCCUGAGAUACAGCAGUCUACAAAACAAAAAGAAAGCAAACAAACAAAACAAAACCCUGUUCUCAUAGACCUUAAUUCUAGAGGAGGACAUAGGUAAUAAAUAAACAACUACAAUAUAAAGUAUAACAGAUCACUGGAUGGCAAAAAGCAAACCAAGGAAGGGGAGGGAAGUGUUGGGGAAUGUAAUUUUAAAUAUAGUGAUGGGAAGCAGGCAGUAAGCUUACUUAGAUGGUGACAAAAGCAAAGACCCAGAGAGGGUAAAAGAGCAAACCAUGUAUAUAUAUAUGACGGAAGAGCAUUCCAGGGAUAUAUCUUUUAGAAUCUGAGGGUGUGGGAAGAGAAAGAUGUUAAACUCCUCUGACAUAAAGAAGAGGAAAAAAAGUGGAAACAUUUUUUUAAAUCAAGAUUUAAAAAAAAAUUACAUUUGUGAUAGGUAGAAAACAAUCUGUCACACACUGCUUUUGGUAGUUGUGUAAGUUUGUACAACCUACCAAAAUGUAAAUCUGACAGUAUACAUCAAAGCCUUAUGAUGGUCGGCAGUCCAUCGAGGAAUCUAUUCUAUGUUGUACAAUCAAGGCGUACUAUGAUAUUUAUUGCAGAACAGAGAGAAAUAGCAUAUACAUUGCUAGUUAAUUGAUUAAAUAAAGCAUGAUUCCUUCAAAAAUUGAGUAAUAUGACAUUAAAAACCACAAUUUCAAACUAUAUUUAAGAAGAUACAAAUAAUUCUUUAUUAUUACUUUUACUCUCAGGAAUGUGUUUGAGUGAUGCAUCUCCAGGCAUCAAGUGAGUAAUCCAAUAUUGAAGAAAAUUAAAAUUUUCCACAAAGUCCCCCUUCUAGAAGAAUGUGCUCAUAUCUUUUGACCAGAAAUGAGUCACAUGACCACACCUAGUUUCAGGUGGCUUGAGGAAAUUGAAUCUUUCUUUUUUUGUUUUAUUUUGUUUUGAGACAAAGUCUCUGUCACCCAGACUGGAGUGUGCAGUAGUGCAAUCUUGGCUCAUUACAAUCUCUACCUCCCAGGCUUAAGCACUCCUCCCACCUUAGCCUUCCUAGUAGCUGGGACUACAGGUGCAUGCCACCAAGCUAAUUUUUUUUUUUUUUUUUUGGUGGAAACAGAGUUUUGCCAUGUUACUCAGGCUGGUCUCAAACUUCUGGGCUCAAGUGAUCUGCCCACCUUGGCCUCCCAAAGUGCUGUGAUUAAAAGUGUGAGCUACCACAUUUGGCCAAAUCUUUAAUUUCUUAACCUUCAUAGUAAAGGAAAUAAAGAGACAUGGGCAUUGAAAAAUGGAUGUUGUACAAACCAACCUGUAGCAUCUAAAAUACUAAAUAAAAAACAGUUUACAAAACUA